GCAGUGUGUCAGAGCUGGCAUUGGCCUGAGGUGGCAUGGCUGCCCUGGCGAGGACAAGUUCCUUGUCCCAUCUGAAGAAGUGGCAUAGGAGAUCUGAGUUUCGGUUCAUGGGCUUUCAGAGGACAGGAGACUUACAGAAUCCAUGUUCUGCUGUGUGUCUUCCCCCCGGCUCAUCUUUUUUUCUUUUAUCAGAAACAUCUGGCCCUGCCCUGGCAACUUUGUAGAAUAAACUUGCUGCUCUUUGUACAGCCUCAGCCUUCCCAGGAGGAGUCUGUGAGGGCAUUAUUAUUAAUGAGGUCACUGACAGCAGUUGCUUGGCUUUCCCAGGGUGGGCACACCUGUGCCCUAGGUUAGGGCACUCGGCUGGUCACUGGAUGCUAUGGGUCUUCAGGGACUAGGCCUGUGAUUUGGGGAGGCUUCUCCAAGUCUUGGUUUCCUUGUCAGAGAGUUGUGGUAAAACACUGGCAAAGGAAUAAUGCAAAAAUAUGAAAUUCUUUUGAAAUUAAGUUGCAAGCAUGUGUCAGCACAGAGUCACUGGAAGUCUUUGUGUGGCCAGAUUUAAAUGAUGGAUCUCUCUUUGUUUGGCCUCUUUUGACCUCUUUAAUCUUCUUUGGCUCUUUGACUGUGUAUAGUGGGUAAACUUGGGCCAAGUCAGUGCAACCUGCCUUUUUUUUCCAGCGUCUUUUGAAUUGAAGUAUAAUGCACAUGGGAAACUGAAAGCAGCAGGUAACCACCAUCCAGAUCCAGUAACAGAUCAUUACCUGAACCAGCCCCGUGUUCUCCUACCCACCACCACCAUCAAGUGUAAUCACUGUCCUGACUAACAGCAUAGGUCUGUUUUUGUACUUAAUAUAAAUAGACUCAUACAGGAUAUAAAAGAUGCCAUUUGUGUCUGGCAUUUUUCAGCCAGUGUUUUACUGUAUUUUGAGAUUCAUCUAUGUGGUUGCAUGUAGUGGUAGGUGGUGCAUUCUUGUUGCUGUAUACUAUCUCUUGCACCACUCUGGCUUGUUUUUGUUUUUAAGAGACAGGGUCUUGCACUGUUGCCCAGGCUGAGUGCAGCAGCGUGAUCAUGGCUCACUACAGCCUUGACCUCCUGGCUUCAAAUGAUCCUCCUCAGCCAAAGUAUUAGGAUUACUGGUGUGAGCCACUGUGCCCAUCCCACCACCCUGUUUUGACUGUGGUUGAUUUAAAGCAGACGAAAGUAGUCAUAAUAAGGCCCCUGACUUCCAGAAGGUAUGGUCCUUUCUAAGUUUCUGUCAAAGGGGCCAAAUAGGAGUGUUGACCUAAUAUAUAGAUGACCCGAUUGUAUCUUCAGGACAAGAACAUGCAUGUUAAGAAAGGUGAAGUUCAAUCAGUUGGUCUUCUAGGGUCUAGAAACUAAAAGGUAGGAUUUUUAGCUGUGGUCAUCUAGGGCACCUGGAGAGACGGUUCUAGAUAAUCAAUUAGAAAUAUCCCAAGACUGGGGAGACAAAGUUCAGCUGUGCCACAGGCAUCCUGCAUCCUUUGCUUUGAUGCUUCUAUGCUUGUGGAGUAACUUUCUUAUCCUAUGUGAUCACUUGAAUUCAGCCCUCUACCAGGAGGGUGUGCCCUGCAGACACAAGUGAUGAACAUUUGCUUAUUCAUGUAUUAUGUAUUUUCUGCUUGCUUACUAAAAGGAUUUAGUGAUUUGGUUCAGCUUUCAGUAAAAAGAUUUCUAGAACGAGAGUCAUCAAACUGGCGAGAUGAUUACUGAAAAACUUGACAGGCCAGGUGUGGUGGCUCAUGCUUGUAAUCCCAGCACUUUGGGAGGCCAAGAUGGAAGGAUUGCUUAAGGCCAGGAGUUUGAGACCAGUCUGGACAACGCAGUGAGACUCUGUCUCUACAGAAAAAAUAAAAUUAAAAAAAUCAGCUGGGUACGAGGGUGCAUACCUAUAGUCUUAGCUACUUGGGAGGCUGCAGUGGAAGGAUCAUGAGCCCAGGAGUUUAAGGCUGCAGCCUAGGAGUUUGAGGCUGCAGUGAACCAUGAUUGCGUCAUUGCACUCCAGCCUGGGCAGCCGAGCAAGACUCUGUCUCUAAAGUUAAACAAACUUGACGAAGCUCCAAGCUUCCUGACAGUCAAGGCAAAAAGGAUAGUUAGUUCUCUUUGAGUCAGUCGUUUUCAUCCCAUCGGCCUAUAACAGGUAGCACAGUGUGUCUGGGCAGCCAGACUUUCUCCUGACACUAACCCUUACUGGGGACUGAAUGGCUAGGGAAGCAUUAGUGAAAGACACAGCAGCUUUACCUGGUGCAGUGGUCUUUAUAGUCUUUCCUGUGAGCCCUUGAUUAAAAGUGAUAGAACUAAACCUAUGAAGCAUUUCAUGGGGAGCUAAUGUAAUGUUGUGAAGGUGAGGAGCUUUCUGUUCCUGGAAUUGGUAAUUUCCCAGGGUCUUAGGGGCUUGCCCAUGCCUCCUGAGCCUUUUCACACUGCUGUCUCUAGGUAAGCAUUUAUCUGCUAAGGUGGCUGAGCUCCAAAAGUAUCCCCUUUGAUUGCCAGUCUCUCAGGCCACUUAAAUCUGUGACACUUCCCAUGGGCUGCCUUGUAUUGUGCCCGACAUUCUUAUUAGACAAGACUCAUCUCUCCACGCAUUCUAGAGACACUCAUUGAUCUAUAAUAUGAGCCAGCUUCUUUGAUAUAAAGUCCUAGAGAGCAGGGCUGUUGAUUUCUUAAAAUUUUUAAGAAUUGUAAUAAAAUAUUAAUCACAAAAUUUACCAUUUUAACCAUUUUAAGUGUACAAUUUAGUGGCAUUAAGUGUGUUAUUCACAUUGCUGUGCAACUACCACCACUAUUCAUUUCCAGAAUUAAUUUCUUGUAAAAUUAUGUUUCUGUACACUAGUGCUUUGUAUUUAAUAGCUGUUCCAUAAAUGCCAUAACAUGGAAGAUGCUGGGGUUGCAACAGUAGUCAGGAUUCAGGGAUUGAAUGAUACGGAUCUUACAGACUUAGACAUUGAAAUUUAAGGUUUCGUUUCGUCUACACUUCCCUUUUAAAACCCUUGAGUACCUUACUCAAGGUAGGAUCUGUAGUACUUCAUAUAAAAACUGUCAAAAUUGGAAUAUUGCUGUCUUCUGGAUGUAAAUAAUUUGAUCAAGGCCAGGUUCCCACAGGGACCAGAUGGGGUGGGCUCAGGAUCCAGGCAGUGGCACCAGUCUUUCAGUUGCAUUGGGCCUGCAGAAUGAGAUGGGCGCUUCUGGGCCAGAAGGGUUGACAUUCAUCCAGGUGAUCCAGAUUCUAGUUUCAACUGUGUGACCUGGGUCGAGGCUGCUCCCCGAUGGGCCUGGUUUCUCUGAGAUCCCUUUCUUGCAGUCACCUCCAGGCCUUUCCUUCCUGGGCUUCCCCAUACCUGGCCAGGACUGUGUAUGGCCCACCCUGCACACUGCAUACUUCGAAGUGGAGCCUCCAUGAAUGUCCCCUUUUGUUCUCUCCAUUUGUUGCUUUGUGACAGUGACACAAUUUCCUCUCCUUUUUUAAGUGCUGGUCUGGAGGAAAAUGCAGGUACUUAAGGGGAUGGGUGUUAAUGGCUUCCCAUUUUGGGUAUUAUCUUAUUUCCUAGAGAGUAUGGGGUUAAUUUGUCUUUAGGGCUUCCCCUGACACCAACCCCAAUUCUGUAGAGGAAGUGGGCAUGUCAGACUGGUAUGUUAUGGGAAAAACUGAAACUGACCAAAAUUACCCAAUGAGGAAGCUCUGAUCUAACCCUUGCUGAAGAAAUAUCAACUAACAGUGCUAUCUCUGUCUAACACGCCCUCGCUUCCUGGGCUGGCAGCUUGGCAGGCAGACGGGAAGGUAACCCGUUCUUCAGCCAGGCUUUGCUCUGGCCUGCCUCCGAUUCCCCAGCCUGGAAUGCCCCCUCCUCCUUUCCUCCUCUCCCAGAUAGAGAUUUAAAGAGAAGCAGCCUUGUCCAUGCCCAUCACAGAAAGAGAAGGAAUAGUUUGGGGAAACAGCCUCUGCUUUGUGACUAAGGAGGGUUGAGAAAUGUCUGUGAUUGCCUGAAGGUGACCCUGGGUGGAGAGAAGCUUUAGAAGAAAGAAGGGGUGGAAGGAAAGGGGGGGUGAUAGAGAACUCUUUUGUCCCCACAGUUAUGCUAAUGACUCUGUCAUGUGGGGCUAUUCAUCCUGUUUUGUGGCAAGGAAGCUGGGGUUCAGAUGAAGAGUCCUCUAAUGUCGCACACCUGUACGAACGCUACCACUAGGAUUUGCAUACUGGUGUUUCUGAUGCCAGAGCACUCCUUUCACCACCACCAGCUACAAAUCAAGGGUUGACCUGAAUGAGUCUGCUUUGAUAGUAUCCAGAAACUUACAUCUCUUAAAAACAAAUGCAGAGUUUGUCUUCCCAACUCCCAGCAGGCUGGAUCAACACAGGAUUACUUCACAGGGUCACACCUGGCCUAAUAUCUUAACCACCGACUCUCAAAGAUUCCAGGCAGAAAAGUGAUAUGCAGUGUUGAUCAGAACAGGGCCAACCACGAUCACGUUAUUGGCAUAUUGGAAACCUCCCAGAGGAGAGGGGAAGGUGUUUGAGCCCCAGCCUUAGAGGUGUCAUUUGGUUAGUCUGGAAUGGAUCCUUGGAAUUCUUACUGUUUUCUUUAAAAGCUCCUCAUGUGAUUCUGAUGUGCAGCAAGUUUGGAAACUCUUAUCACAAGUGACAGAAUGGAGAUUAGGCAGAAGUAUCAGAAAGCAGAUUUAUCUUUGAUUGAGGAAACUCUUUGAAACAAGUAGAGCUGUUCAAAAAUGGAAUUUAGAGAAAUAGCGAGCCUCUCAGGCUUGGAAGUAUUCAAACCUAGGCCACAUGACUAUCAAUUGGGUGGAGAGAGACAAACUAGAUAAAUUCGAAUACUAUGUUUAGUGGGAUUUUCGAACUAGUUACCCUAAGGGCCUUUCCUUUCUAUGGAUGAAUACUUUUCAGCUGCAGUCCCACUGCUGUGUGUACAUCUGCUAUCACCUGCUUGGCUUUCUCCUUUGACUUUGGGCCUGGUGCUCCCUCCCACUGAUGGCACUGUGGGUGAAAGUUGGCAAGAUUCUGAAAAUUGCAUUCAUCUCCUUCUCAAUCCAGGAAAAUCAUCUUUGUAUGGUGGCUGCUUCUUGUUUCUGACUUCUGCUUCCCUUGGCUACCAACACAGCAGUGCCUACCAGGGCUGGGUGGGCUCCACUGGUGUGUUUAGGAAACUGUGGCAUUAAGUGAUUAUUAAUUAUCCCUUCCUGAGUGGCCCUAAUAAGCUGAGUGGACACAUCAUCAUGCCCUGGUGCCAUCUGUUCUCAAGUUUUGAGAGUUCAAAGAGCUCUGAUGUGAAAGAGGGGAAGUUUGGGCCAAGCUACUGGCCUGGACAUUUUUCACUGUUUCAUAUCCACAGCUGUUUCAUAUCUUCUCUCUUAGUCUCCUCAUGUGAUGGAGAGGAAAAUAAGGUCCCAGGGUCAUCCAAGAAACCACAGGGCAGGCUGGGAGUGCCCAUCCACACUAAGAGGGGCCCACAGGACAGGCGAGGGUGGCUGUCCUGACGGCCUGGCAGUGGGGCCAGACAGACCUCUGUGGAAUCCCAUCUCUGCCCCUCAUUACCCAAGUGAUCUAUAAAACGGAGGUGCAGAAGUUUUACGAAGACAAUGGAGAACAGGUCAGGAAAGCCGGAAGUGCCUGACAGGUUGACCAGUAUCUCUACCACAUGCGCCUCUCUGAUGAGACCCUCUUGGAGAUCUCUAAGCGGUUCCGCAAGGAGAUGGAGAAAGGGCUUGGAGCCACCACUCACCCUACUGCAGCAGUGAAGAUGCUGCCCACCUUUGUGAGGUCCACUCCAGAUGGGACAGAACACGGAGAGUUCCUGGCUCUGGAUCUUGGAGGGACCAACUUCCGUGUGCUUUGGGUGAAAGUAACGGACAAUGGGCUCCAGAAGGUGGAGAUGGAGAAUCAGAUCUAUGCCAUCCCUGAGGACAUCAUGCGAGGCAGUGGCACCCAGCUGUUUGACCACAUUGCCGAAUGCCUGGCUAACUUCAUGGAUAAGCUACAAAUCAAAGACAAGAAGCUCCCACUGGGUUUUACCUUCUCGUUCCCCUGCCACCAGACUAAACUAGACGAGAGUUUCCUGGUCUCAUGGACCAAGGGAUUCAAGUCCAGUGGAGUGGAAGGCAGAGACGUUGUGGCUCUGAUCCGGAAGGCCAUCCAGAGGAGAGGGGACUUUGAUAUCGACAUUGUGGCUGUGGUGAAUGACACAGUUGGGACCAUGAUGACCUGUGGUUAUGAUGACCACAACUGUGAGAUUGGUCUCAUUGUGGGCACGGGCAGCAACGCCUGCUACAUGGAAGAGAUGCGCCACAUCGACAUGGUGGAAGGCGAUGAGGGGCGGAUGUGUAUCAAUAUGGAGUGGGGGGCCUUCGGGGACGAUGGCUCGCUCAACGACAUUCGCACUGAGUUUGACCAGGAGAUUGACAUGGGCUCACUGAACCCGGGAAAGCAACUGUUUGAGAAGAUGAUCAGUGGGAUGUACAUGGGGGAGCUGGUGAGGCUUAUCCUGGUGAAGAUGGCCAAGGAGGAGCUGCUCUUUGGGGGGAAGCUCAGCCCAGAGCUUCUCAACACCGGUCGCUUUGAGACCAAAGACAUCUCAGACAUUGAAGGGGAGAAGGAUGGCAUCCGGAAGGCCCGUGAGGUCCUGAUGCGGUUGGGCCUGGACCCGACUCAGGAGGACUGCGUGGCCACUCACCGGAUCUGCCAGAUCGUGUCCACACGCUCCGCCAGCCUGUGCGCAGCCACCCUGGCCGCCGUGCUGCAGCGCAUCAAGGAGAACAAAGGCGAGGAGCGGCUGCGCUCUACUAUUGGGGUCGACGGUUCCGUCUACAAGAAACACCCCCAUUUUGCCAAGCGUCUACAUAAGACCGUGCGGCGGCUGGUGCCCGGCUGCGAUGUCCGCUUCCUCCGCUCCGAGGAUGGCAGUGGCAAAGGUGCAGCCAUGGUGACAGCAGUGGCUUACCGGCUGGCCGAUCAACACCGUGCCCGCCAGAAGACAUUAGAGCAUCUGCAGCUGAGCCAUGACCAGCUGCUGGAGGUCAAGAGGAGGAUGAAGGUAGAAAUGGAGCGAGGUCUGAGCAAGGAGACUCAUGCCAGUGCCCCCGUCAAGAUGCUGCCCACCUACGUGUGUGCUACCCCGGACGGCACAGAGAAAGGGGACUUCUUGGCCUUGGACCUUGGAGGAACAAAUUUCCGGGUCCUGCUGGUCCGUGUUCGGAAUGGGAAGUGGGGUGGAGUGGAGAUGCACAACAAGAUCUACGCCAUCCCGCAGGAGGUCAUGCACGGCACCGGGGACGAGCUCUUUGACCACAUUGUCCAGUGCAUCGCGGACUUCCUCGAGUACAUGGGCAUGAAGGGCGUGUCCCUGCCUCUGGGUUUUACCUUCUCCUUCCCCUGCCAGCAGAACAGCCUGGACGAGGUAACAGCACCUUCCUGGAGGGCUCUCCUGUGGGCUUUAUUGACUCUAAACAAAACCAGCCAGAGCAUCCUCCUCAAGUGGACAAAAGGCUUCAAGGCAUCUGGCUGCGAGGGCGAGGACGUGGUGACCCUGCUGAAGGAAGCGAUCCACCGGCGAGAGGAGUUUGACCUGGAUGUGGUUGCUGUGGUGAACGACACAGUCGGAACUAUGAUGACCUGUGGCUUUGAAGACCCUCACUGUGAAGUUGGCCUCAUUGUUGGCACGGGCAGCAAUGCCUGCUACAUGGAGGAGAUGCGCAACGUGGAACUGGUGGAAGGAGAAGAGGGGCGGAUGUGUGUGAACAUGGAAUGGGGGGCCUUCGGGGACAAUGGAUGCCUAGAUGACUUCCGCACAGAAUUUGAUGUGGCUGUGGAUGAGCUUUCACUCAACCCCGGCAAGCAGAGGUUCGAGAAAAUGAUCAGUGGAAUGUACCUGGGUGAGAUUGUCCGUAACAUUCUCAUCGAUUUCACCAAGCGUGGACUACUCUUCCGAGGCCGCAUCUCAGAGCGGCUCAAGACAAGGGGCAUCUUUGAAACCAAGUUCUUGUCUCAGAUUGAGAGUGACUGCCUGGCCCUGCUGCAAGUCCGAGCCAUCCUGCAACACUUAGGGCUUGAGAGCACCUGUGACGACAGCAUCAUUGUUAAGGAGGUGUGCACUGUGGUGGCCCGGCGGGCAGCCCAGCUCUGUGGCGCAGGCAUGGCCGCUGUGGUGGACAGGAUACGAGAAAACCGUGGGCUGGACGCUCUCAAAGUGACAGUGGGUGUGGAUGGGACCCUCUACAAGCUACAUCCUCACUUUGCCAAAGUCAUGCAUGAGACAGUGAAGGACCUGGCUCCGAAAUGUGAUGUGUCUUUCCUGCAGUCAGAGGAUGGCAGCGGGAAGGGGGCGGCGCUCAUCACUGCUGUGGCCUGCCGCAUCCGUGAGGCUGGACAGCGAUAGAACCCCUGAAAUCGGAAGGGACUUCCUCUUUCUCUCCUUCUUCCCUGUUUUAAAUUAUAAGAUGUCAUCCCCUUGUGUCAGAGACAGACCCCUUGGCUUUUGCUUGGCAGAGAGGACCCCACUGGACUGGGUUUUGUCUCUGCAUCUCAUUGUAGAGCUUGGUGGCUGAGCUUGGCCCUAUUAAGAUAAAUAGAGUUCCAAAUAAGGAUUUGUUCACAUGCAUCAUAACCAUUCCCAUUGGUUCUCCUAAAACAUGAAAAUUAUCUCCCUUAGUAAUCCCCCUUGCCAAAUUCCAUGUCCCUGUAUAAUUCUACAGGAUGGGGACACUAAUGAAGAUACGGUUGCUUCACCUUGGAGCCUGAACAUGACAUUUCUAAGUGGGGUGCAUCCCCCAGCACUGAUGUUGUUACUGAUUCUCCUGUCAGAGAUCUGGGAGGUCUCCACUGAGGAUGUGAGCCUGAUUAUCCUAUAGGCAGACGUGGGGAGGGUGGAGGGGUGACAGUGGAGGAAAAUCCAUGGAUAUCCACGCAGCAGCCCCUCUUUAACCUCAUCUACAAGCAUUUGCCCUGUGGAUUCCAGCAUUUGCCAUUCCUGGAAUCAAGGAAUCCUGAGUCUGGGCAAUGAAACCAAAGCCAGGAGUUGACGCAUCCUGCAGUUGGGCCAGCUGUCGCAUCUCAGCGGGGCGCACAUGUUAUCCACAAGCAAUGGACCUUUGGGGAAGGGGGAGUUUUUAGUUUGUUUUACAAAUUUUUCCUGCAAAAGUGGAAUCACUGUAUUUUCAUUUUAAUUUAUAUUUGAAAUUUUAUUUAGUUCUUGAGUAGAUCUGCUUCUUCAUCUUGACAUGUAAUGAAUGGUCAGUUGUACGUAAUGUAUUUAUAUGUUAAUUUGUUAUGUAUAUAGAUGUGCAAGUCUUGUCAGAAUUGGCCUCAGUGUAGUUAAAGGGCAGAAGGGGAAGAUACUGACUAGUCAUAGAAAUACCUCAUUCGCCUGUGGGAAGAGAAGGGAAGCCUCUUCAGGGUGAGUGAAUGGCAAAGCGGUUGCUUCUGGCUCCUCCUUCCCCUGUGGUCUUGGAAGUGUGUGGAAGGCAGGGACAGAGAUGGAGGCCGAGCCAAUAGACUGAAGAGACCACAGCAAUUGGCUCCUCCAUCUAGAGAUUUUCUUGGCAGUAUUCCAUGGGAUGUUAAGCAAAGGAAACCAAAGGAAUCGUUUCAAAUGGACUCAUGGCUUAGAAAUCUUUAUUCUUAGGGCAGUCAGUAGUAUUCUAAAGCUUUCUGACAAGAUAAAGGAAGUCACCAAAAUUUCUUUUUUUAAAUUGUAUCUAAUCCUCAACAACAAACCAAAACAGAACAAUUAAACAGCCAAAUAAAACCUCAGGGACAACAUUUUUGGUGUAUUUGAGCCCUCCCAGCAAGUUUCACCUUGGGUUUGUAUUUUAAAUGUUUUACAAGAAUUGUCCAUGUGCUUCCCUAGGCUGAGCUGGCAUUGGUCUGCUGACCUGUUUUUGUGUUUUUCUUUUUUUUAUACACAACAUUUAUUUCAAACUAUUGGGAGGGAUGAGAGUGGCUUAAAAACUUCCAUCCCUACUUUUCAAGAGUGCAGUUGAUUCUGAAUCUGAAAGCCCGCCUCUGUCCUAAAAUACAAACAAGCACAGACAUUAAACCUGGAUACUAUAUGAUAAAGAGGGAUGUAACUAUUGAAUUGGAUACAAGGAUCAGAAUGGAAAGAAACUCACGAUGAAAUUGAACCUGGUUUUUGUAUAUUUAUCAAACUUGUGCUGAGAAUAGUGUCUGAUUAUACGACUUUUAAGCAAAGUUGGGUGUAAUUAGGUGAAAACAGCCCAGGUCCUCCCGGGAGCACAGAGGGGCUAGGGGCUGGUCCUUCUCGUUUGCUCUAGUCUUGCUUUGCUGUCUGGUGUAGCUCCUCUGCUGCUCCCAUCUGCACUAAUUGACCCAAAACGUGGGUAUUUCCUGCUACACAAAAGCCAAAAGGUUUCAUGUAGAUUUUAGUUCACUAAAGGGUGCCCACAAAAUAGAGAUUAAUUUUAACUUAAAUUUUAAGCUUGAAGAUUAGGUACUAUCUGUGAAGUUACACUUUUUUUUUUUUUUUUAAAGGUAGAGAUGUGUGUGUGUGUAGGUAUUAAAGAUGUGUUGUUGGUUUCCAAAAAGGAACACUGGAAAAUAAAUUUUGAAUGUUUAUGUUCUCAGAAUCAGGUUGACAGUCCCUUGCUGACAUGGCUUUGCUUUGUGUAAAUACAGUGGAUCUCAAUCUUCGGGGUGUGAUGAAUAGCGAAUCAUCUCAAAUCCUUGAGCACUCAGUCUAGUGAAGAUGUUGUCAUUAUGUACAAUACAUAACUAGUUUAAUUAACUAUGUGAUGUUAACUAUUAUUAAUAAAUUUUAACAUUUUCCAAAAUAAUCAAA